ACCCCUGAGGAUCCCGGUCCACGCGGAGGAGUGGGGCUUUUCACCGCCGCCGCCGCCGCCCUCGGACCUCUCCCGGGAUACUUCACAUUUCCCUAGGGACGGGAGCCCGAGGGGUCCGUUCGGCCCUCUUCCUCUCGCUGGGCCGACACCCCGCUGUAGGACCGUAACCCUUAGUCCCAAUGCCUCCGUAAGCGGAGUUGAGUGGGUGCCUGUGGUUGGAGCUGUGGAGGUGUCCCCGGUGGCGAGCGCGGCCAGAACUGCGGUCACUUAAGUUUUCCGUGUGCGGGUUGCAAGGAGCGUGCGUGCGUCUGGUAUAAUUUGGCUUCCUGAGAUUCUGCCUUAGCAAGAAAGGAGUGGGAAAUACCCUUGGAAAGAAAACUAAAACAGUAAGAAAGCCAAAACUUAUUUUUACAUGGUUGUCAGCACAUUUACCGAUAUGGACACUUUUCCCAAUAAUUUUCCUCCUGGUGGAGACAGUGGAUUGACAGGUUCUCAGUCGGAGUUCCAGAAAAUGUUAAUUGAUGAAAGGUUACGAUGUGAGCAUCAUAAAGCUAAUUAUCAGACACUGAAGGCUGAACACACAAGGUUGCAGAAUGAACAUGUAAAGUUACAAAAUGAACUCAAGCACCUGUUUAAUGAAAAGCAAACUCAGCAGGAAAAACUUCAGCUCCUGCUUGAAGAACUAAGAGGAGAAUUAGUAGAGAAAACUAAAGAUUUAGAAGAAAUGAAACUGCAGAUAUUAACUCCACAAAAAUUGGAAUUGCUAAGAGCCCAAAUACAACAAGAAUUAGAAACUCCAAUGAGAGAACGUUUUAGGAAUCUAGAUGAAGAGGUAGAAAAGUAUAGAGCUGUAUAUAAUAAGCUUCGCUAUGAACAUACAUUUCUCAAGUCAGAAUUUGAACACCAGAAGGAAGAGUAUGCACGUAUUUUAGAUGAAGGAAAAAUAAAAUAUGAAUCAGAGAUUGCAAGACUGGAGGAAGAUAAAGAAGAACUACGUAACCAGCUGCUUAAUGUUGAUCUCACAAAAGACAGCAAACGAGUGGAACAACUUGCUCGAGAAAAAGUCUAUUUGUGUCAAAAAUUAAAAGGUUUAGAGGCUGAAGUAGCGGAAUUAAAGGCUGAAAAGGAGAAUUCUGAGGCUCAGGUGGAAAAUGCCCAAAGAAUACAGGUGCGGCAGUUGGCUGAGAUGCAGGCUACAGUCAGAUCCCUGGAGGCUGAAAAACAAUCAGCUAAUUUACGGGCAGAACGUUUGGAAAAAGAGCUACAAUCAAGCAGUGAACAAAAUACCUUUUUAAUUAAUAAAUUGCAUAAAGCUGAACGAGAAAUAAAUACAUUGUCCAGUAAAGUAAAAGAACUUAAACAUUCAAACAAACUGGAAAUAACAGACAUCAAACUGGAGACAGCAAGAGCUAAGAGUGAGCUAGAAAGAGAAAGGAAUAAGAUUCAAAGUGAACUGGAUGGAUUACAGUCAGACAAUGAAAUUCUCAAAGCAGCUGUUGAACAUCACAAAGUGCUCUUAGUAGAAAAGGAUCGUGAAUUAAUACGUAAAGUACAAGCUGCCAAAGAAGAAGGUUAUCAAAAACUUGUGGUAUUACAAGAUGAAAAGUUAGAACUCGAGAACAGAUUAGCAGAUUUGGAGAAAAUGAAAGUGGAACAUGAUGUCUGGAGGCAAUCUGAAAAGGAUCAGUAUGAAGAGAAAUUGCGGGCUUCACAGAUGGCAGAAGAGAUCACCAGGAAGGAGCUUCAGAGUGUUAGGUUAAAACUUCAGCAACAAAUUGUGACUAUUGAAAAUGCAGAGAAGGAAAAAAAUGAAAAUUCUGACCUAAAACAGCAAAUCAGUAGUUUGCAGAUCCAAGUGACUUCACUUGCACAGUCAGAGAAUGACUUGCUGAAUUCAAACCAAAUGCUGAAGGAAAUGGUGGAGAGAUUAAAACAAGAAUGCCGAAAUUUUAGAAGCCAAGCUGAAAAAGCGCAACUAGAAGCUGAAAAGACAUUGGAAGAGAAACAGAUACAGUGGUUGGAAGAAAAGCAUAAGCUUCAUGAGCGUAUCACAGACAGAGAAGAAAAGUACAAUCAAGCUAAGGAGAAACUGCAGCGAGCUGCAAUUGCCCAGAAAAAGAGAAAAUCUCUUCAUGAAAACAAAUUGAAAAGACUACAAGAGAAAGUAGAAGUCUUGGAGGCAAAGAAAGAAGAAUUGGAAACAGAAAAUCAGGUCUUAAAUAGACAAAAUGUUCCUUUUGAAGACUAUACAAGGCUUCAAAAAAGACUAAAAGAUAUACAGAGAAGACAUAAUGAAUUUCGAAGUCUAAUUUUGGUUCCUAACAUGCCUCCAACAGCAUCUAUCAAUCCUGUUAGCUUUCAGUCAUCAGCCAUGGUUCCAAGCAUGGAACUACCAUUUCCUCCUCAUAUGCAGGAGGAACAACAUCAAAGGGAACUCUCUCUACUUCGCAAAAGACUAGAAGAACUGGAAACAACACAAAGAAAACAACUAGAGGAACUUGGAUCUUCCGGAGAAUGAUGUUCUUGGAGAACAGGCAGAUCAAAAGAGGGCCGAAUGAAAGUCAAGAGAAAAGCCUAGUUCUUAUACCAACCUGAAUUAAAGAGAGAAGAAACAAGAAAGAAAAUUCAGUUUCAGAAGUUCCGUAGAAGCAGCAUGAGGCCAGUUAGAAGUGCAAGUCUGAGGGAAACUUCUGAUCUAAGCUUCUUUCCAAGCCAGAGUCAGCAGCCCUGGGACAUUCUGCCUGACGUUCCCCUUUGAGCUGCGCUUGCCCAUCCAGCCUCCCCUCUUCACUCUGCUCCCCUUUUCCUUUCCCCACAAAGAUCCAUAAAUCACAGCUUCCUGGAUCAAGGGAUCUGCUACUCUAACAGAAGAGUAAGGGGUGGAGGACAGGGUAACGAGAGCCUUUUUCCAUUUAAAAAAAAAAAAAAGUAAUGGAGAUAAUUUUCUCAAAUUUAGGUUUCUCUCACCAAUUUUUCUAUACUUGCUAGCAUUUGCUAACGUUUUGUCCAUCCUAGAAUCAAGUAUGAAGAGCUGUCUGAUUUAGCCCAAGAUAACUGAUUUUAGUAUUCACAGUAUUUGCGGGUGCAGGGUUGGGGGUGGGGGUGGGUGUUGUGUGUUGGCAAAGAGCCCCAUGAGUUUCAGACUUGUAAAUAGUGGCAAGGCAUUUCCAUUGCUGUGUCCCAGAAGGGGAGGAAAGAGGCCAACCUGUUUGUGGGUUUGUGGGAGGGAGGAUUCUGGUUCCUAUUCUCUACUAUGUCAAGCUCUAGAUUAAAGGCCAACAAACUUUCUGCAAAGGGCCAGAAAGUAUUUAAGACUUAAAACUCAUAUGAUCUCUGUGACAACUACUCCACUCUGCACUGUAGCAGGAAAGCAGCUAUAGACAAUAAGGAAAUGAACAGGUGUUCCAAUAGAACUUUAUAAAAAUAGGCAGAGGGGCCACAUUUGGCCCACAGGCUGUUGUUUGCUGGUCCCUGCUCUAGAUAACAGUACCUUCAAAUGGAAUGCUAACUUUGACAAUAGCAACAAGACAAAUCUGGAAAAUGCUUUCUAUCUCCGCCAUGACUUGUGAUAAAAUUUACCAUUCUCUGAGGGGUACAAAUAUAAAUAAUGAUCCUAACAAUAACAUAAUAGAGUCACAUUUGAGCUAUAAAGAAAAAAAGUAAAUACUUUUAUAUUUAGAUAACUAAAUUAUUUUCUAAUUCCAAGAUUACAGGCAUGAGAAGAAAGUGUAUGAAGAGGAAAGUCAUUUAAAGCACCCAUUACAUGUUAAUUUUUCAUUUUCCAUGACUUGCCAUCAACGAGGGAAUGACUUACCUAAAAUGAUUGUAAAAAGUGGUUUCACUCUUUGAUCAGGAAGCUCAGAACACUAACUAUGAAGUUAGUAAUGGUUUCAGUACUAUUGCAAGUCAUAAUGGAAAUGAUUUGCACUAUGGUAGAGAGAAAAAUAAAAAGCUCAAGAAUUGUUAAUUAACUUCACUGUUUCUCCACAAAUGGUAGGAGUAUUAAAAACAAGAUUGCUGAAGUGCAAACAUCAGGAUUUAAUGAACAAUGGAAUGUAAUUGAAGUAACAGAGAAUGACUUAAUCGGGACAGUGGGUUGUUUAAUUACGGGGCUAAUGGAUCUUCUGCAAGGACAAACUAAAUGGAACAGAAGCAGCCAGCACUGGUAGGCAGAGCACUGUUAAAGGAAGUAUACUAGUAAGAAACUCCUGGUGGAGACACCUAGGGCUCUGUUGUAUAUGAGAUAUUUUAUUAAACGUAAUUGUCCCAAAAUGGUAACUGCUAGAGAAAGAGACAGACUGGGGUAGGCUGGCAUAAACCUUCAAUAAAUCAAAUUGGAGGCAUUAAUAUUUCUGCAGGCAUGUACUUGUGCUUUUUCAAGAAUUUCUAAUAAUCUUGAAAACUUUCUUAUAGAUAGGAGAAUGAAGGCAAUAAUAUUUUUGUCGGAACAGUUUUCCAGGGUGCCAAGAUGCUCUCUCUCAGAUACAGCAGAUUGGCAAGCUCGUUUUCUAAGAGUUCAAAAAACCAUUUCACACUUAACUUUGAUUACAAGUCAACCUUCUCUUGCUAAUUCAGCACGCUUGCUACGAGUUAUUGGUUUUUCUCAUCUCUUCCUGAAAGUGAAGCAAAUGUCCCUUCUCCCAUGUGAAAUCCUCAAACUUUCACUAACUCCUCCAAAGUUCCACUCUUGACAAAACGUAAGCUGAGUGAGUCUGAGAUACUCCAUCAACAAAAUCAAACAUGUUCAAAAUUUUGCAAAGGGGAAAAAAACCCAGCAGAGCAAUAGGUCUUAUUAUCGGCCGGAUGCAGUUGCUCACACCUGUAAUCCCAGCACUUCGGGAGGACAAGGCAGGUGGAUCACUUGAGGCCAGGAGUUCAAGACCAGGCUAGCCAACACGGCGAAAACCCGUUUCUACUAAAAAUACAAGCAUUAGCCUGGCAUGAUGGCAGGUGCCUAUAAUCCCAGGUAUUUGGGAGGCUGAGGCAGGAGAAUCGCUUGAACCCCAGAGGCGGAGGUUGCAGUGAGCCAAGACUGCGCCACUGCACUCCAGCCUGCACUAGAGUGGUAUUCCUUAAAUUAAAAAAAAAAAAAAAAAAAAAAAAGGUCUUAUUCUCUUCCAGCUGUCUGAUCUGAAUUCCUAGAUAUUAAGGAAAGACUAAAGUCCUGUGUGUGCACAGCCCUACCCCUGGUGCUGACAUUAGGGAGGAUGCAGAUAUCAGGGCAUUCUGUCUCACUGUUGCCUCAUUAAACACCAGCCUGGAAUGCUUGAUAGAGAAGGAUGGUUUCUUAUGGUCCUGGAGGAAGUAUGGCUCUAGGGGACUUUGCUUGGAUUUUUGGCAAGACAGAGGAAUUUUCUUCUCAAUAUGCAAGAAGAGAACAUUACUUCCCAGGGCCUCUUUGUUAGUGUCAUGAUUUCAUGUAUAAGAAAUUGGCAAGAUGCCUUUAUGUUCUAGAAAAUCCCCCACACCUCAGGGAGAACACAUCCUCAUCUGAGAGGUGUGAAAGCUAACUUUUAGAUUGCUAUAUGAGGUGCUGUGCUUCUGAGCAUUUAGCUGAACACGAGUGUGGGGGCCUUUUUUCCAAACGUGUCCCUGCCUUGGCACCAGGUUCUGUCAUUUCAAGUGGUUCGUGAGGAUGCUCUUGAUUUCCGACUUUCCUUUCCUUGAAAGAAUCUGCCCCCAACCUCCCACCUCCCCAGCACACAAGGACACACAGAAUCAGUUUGUUCACCGCACCUUGGUUUUCAAUUACAUAAACCACCUCAGGCAAAUUUGGGAAAUCAAGUCCUAAAAUGGCUGGGUGUACAUGCUUGGGAGGGGUAGGUGGGGGAAGUGAAAAAGAAGGGGAGGAGGGAAGGGAGGAAGAAAGAAAAUUAGAAAUAUGGUGGUUCAGGCUGGGGGAAAUGCCUGAAAGGAAAUGAAAAACUUAAAUUUUUUAUAUUGACCUUCUGCUAACAGUUUGUCACACAAGCAUAGAACGGAUCAUGUGCCUUCUCUGCAGCUUCUCGUACAACUGCCAACCAUGAAAGGGGGGCUGGGCCAGGCCCCAUAAGAGGCACUAACAAUCAUUUUUAAAGGCAAGGCCCCUAAAAACAAGUGGCCCAUUCCUUUUCAAGGCUCAAAUCUUAUGUACCGGCAAAUCUGAAUUUGAAAAGGAAGAUUUAUGUGGAUUUCUGAAAUCAUGAUUUUCCAUUACCCUUUUCCCCAGGGGCUAUAAAGAAAAAAAAAUUUCAAGAGUCGACAUGAAUUCCUUCAGCAUCAAGUAACAUUAUGAUGAUGAGUCGAGUGUUAACAAAUCAGAAACACAUGGUCUUAAUUGACUGUGAAAUAAAUAAUGUUUCGAAAUGAAAGGGAGAAAACACGUUCAGAUGUAAAGCAUUAAAAAGGCUUCAAAACCUCAAAAGUUGCCUCAGACAUCUGACCUCUUCCUGAUUCCAACCCAUCUUCUCCUUUCCUGUCUUUCCUGUUUGGGUCCGGUGUUGUCUCAUGACUGAAAUGCUGGAGGAUUCCCGACUAUAAUCAUUUGCAAAUAUUUCUCUUUGGAGACCUUUGGGGCUUCUAAAACGUCUUAAAGUAAAGGCAUGAACAUCUUCUAGGUUAGGAAUAACAAGCCCAGGAUCAGCGAAAGGUGAGUCAACAGGCCCUGUGCAAAGUUUGUCUCUUGUUCUCCAAGAUACCCAGUGGUGUCCAGGCUGAACACACAUCAGAGAUAUCUGGAAGGUUUACAAAAUACAUCCACGCCUGGGCUCCCUCCCCAGAGAUUCUGAUUCAGUCAGUCCCGAGGGAAAGCCCGGGCACUGGUAUAUUUGCACCUGCAUUUUAAACAAGGGUUCAAUGAGAUCUGGAUCAAAUGGAAUAAAGUUUUAGGUAGCACUCACAUGCCUGGCAAUGUUCUAAGUGCUUUUUAUAAUACUGACUCUUAAUCCUCAAAACACCUCAUGAGAUGGGUAGGAACCAUGACCAUCAUUUCCAUUUCACAUGUGAGGAGAAUGAGGCAUAGAGAGGUUUAGAAACUUGCCCAACAUUACACAGCUAACCAGUGGCAGAGGCAGGAUUCCAAAAUGUCUGGCCCCAGAGUCCAUGCUGUUAACCACUCUACCAACAGUUGUUAAGCAGCACCCGCAGCAUCAGGAAGCUGGUUAGGGAAGUGAAUUCUCAGGCCACAGCCUGGAUUUACUGCAUCGGAAACUCCAGCAUGCUGCCUAGCGACUGGUGUUUAGUGAGCUUUCUGGGCGAUUCUGCUAGAUGCUCAAGUUUGAGAACCAAUGCAGCCCACUCUCCGGCCUCUCAGAUGUGGAUGGGUGUAUUGAUACAAUUCAGAACGCUGAGAAGUGUUGACUUUCAGCUCAGCUUCCCGCUCUCGGAUGGCAGCUGUGCAUGGUGCCAUCUUUGAUGGAGAAGUGAGCCGCAUCUGGCAGUGGCAGAAAACUUGAAACAGCUGACCUACGGACUAUUCUCCCACCAGAGGACAUAACCAUAACACGCUCCACGGCAAAGUGGUGCCUUCUCCAAUUAGGGAAUGAAUUCUUCCCAGAUGACACUGCAGUCCCCACCAUCCAGAGCAAAGCCACAGAAGACUCAGCUCUCUUAAUGAGCAAUUCCCAAACCCCACUGUAAUCUUUUCCUCCUCCACUAACGAGAUCGUGAAGAAGCCCAGAAUCUUCAUAAAGCUAAAGAUCAAACCAAAACACAGCAAUCUCUUCUCCAAGUCUCUACUAACAGAAAAGCAUAGAAAAUUCCUAAUUCUAAAGUUACCUUCCCUGCUUGGCUCCCUCUCUGAAAUUCCCAAAUGUGCCCCAAACUGGGCUUUCUUUCUUUCUUUAGGAAGAGCAUGGGGUGGGUGCGGUGGGGAUGAAUUAGAAAGAAGUUCUCAAGCGGGUGAAACCCUCCAGCAGCUAGGCAAUCAUCUUCCUGUAGUGAUUUACAGCGUUCCUCUAAAAAUAUCUAUGAGAUCACAGUACAUUAAGUGCAUGACACCAAACAUUUGUAACUAAUCCAUGAAAAUAAAGGGCGUCACGUUGCAUGGGGAA